AGUGGUAGCGCGGGGACUGGCUGGGAAGCGGUCGGUCGAGUGUGGCCUGUGUGGACUCGCAUCUUGCCCGAAGCCGGGCGGAGGAGAGCUCAAGCUAAGGGUGAUCAGCCCAUGACCUAAACCUCCAGACAAAAUAAAACGGAAAAUUUGCUAGAAUCAAGAAUGAUGGAUCCAUGUUCAGUUGGAGUCCAGCUUCGUACUACAAAUGAGUGCCAUAAAACCUACUAUACUCGUCACACAGGUUUUAAGACUUUGCAAGAAUUGUCAUCAAAUGAUAUGCUUUUACUUCAACUUAGAACUGGAAUGACACUUUCUGGGAACAAUACAAUUUGCUUUCAUCAUGUAAAAAUUUACAUUGACAGAUUUGAGGAUUUACAGAAGUCAUGUUGUGACCCAUUUAACAUACACAAGAAAUUAGCCAAAAAAAAUUUGCAUGUAAUUGACUUAGAUGAUGCCACUUUUCUGAGUGCUAAAUUUGGAAGACAGCUUGUACCUGGUUGGAAGCUUUGUCCAAAAUGCACACAGAUAAUCAAUGGAAGUGUGGAUGUUGAUACUGAAGACCGCCAGAAAAGGAAACCUGAGUCAGAUGUAUGUGUAAUAGUCAUUUUUUUCUACAUUGUGAAUUCUACCAUGUAGGAUUUUGCUUAACUAUAAGAAAAUCAUAUUUACAUUAUUACUAAAUUUGUUAGCAUACAGUGAAUUAAAAGGAGGGGUGAAAGUGGAUGAUGUUUCUAAAUAUUAUUCACAUAUACUGAAGGUCAAGAUUGGGGGAUAAAGAAAGUAGGCCUGGGAAAGUAAUAAUAAAAUAUGCCUAAGACUCCAAGCUACAACUUUUAGUGCGAAGACUUUAGGAGUGGGUUUUAGAAUAUUCUGGCCAAGCCAGGAUUUAGUUUCUUUUCUGAUACCAAAGUAACUACACGGGACAUGGCAACCACCAAGGGUCUUUGCAGCAGGAUGACUUCGCCUUUAUAUGAAGGACUUGGAAAUCACUGCUUUAAAAGGAACAUUAGAGAGGGAAGAACUGCUAAAGCUUUGAGGUCAUUACAAUUUACGAAUCCAGGAAGGCAAACUGAAUUUGCUCCAGAAACUGGUAAAAGAGAAAAAAGAAGGCUUACAAAAAAUGCAACCGCUGGUUCAGACAGACAAGUGAUACCAGCAAAGAGUAAGGUCUAUGAUAGCCAGGGUCUCCUGAUUUUUAGUGGGAUGGACCUCUGUGACUGCCUGGAUGAAGACUGCUUAGGAUGUUUCUAUGCUUGUCCUGCCUGUGGUUCUACCAAGUGUGGAGCUGAAUGCCGCUGUGACCGCAAGUGGCUGUAUGAGCAAAUUGAAAUUGAAGGAGGAGAAAUAAUUCAUAAUAAACAUGCUGGAUAAUCUGCGGUACCAAACUAUGGAGCCUUUAAAGGUCUUUAUUUCUAAAAAUCUGUUACUCUAAGAUACAUUUUAAGCUUGAUUAUCAUAUGACAAAGAUUUUAAAACCAUCUCAGUGUGCCCUAAUUUUUCAUCUUGGGUGCUUUAAGAUUCACUAUUUGAUAUAAAUUCAGAUAGGCUAUUUUUCAGUAGUCAGCGUUAAGCCUGUCUGGAUCAAUAUAAACAAGUAGGGUGUAGGCAGUCCUCUAUUUGCAUGUUUCCCAUGGGCACAAAUUUCAGUGACCUAGAUUUAGUUUAAAUACCAGUUUCCUUACCAGGAAGGAAAGAAAACUGGUAAGGAAACUGUUGUUGUUAAAAUCUAGGUUAAAAUUUUAGUUAGCACAUUGUAACUGAGUAAUUACAUGAAGUACAAACCUCUCUGCUAGCUCUUCAGUCUACAAAUCGCUAUGUAAAUAACAGAUAUGCUUCAUGAUUGUGACCAGUCAUGUUAUUUCUUUCAAAUUCUUCCAGUGGUUUGUCCCUGUGCAUCUGUUAAUUCAGUUCACGUACAGCAGAGCAUGUAGUUAUGCUGUCUCUCUGUCAUCUACUUGACAUUCUAUAGAAGUGAACACUCGAAAGAACUGGUCAACAAAGAUGAAAGUGCAGCAAAGCAAUGAAAAAUGAUAACACUGGAAGUGAAAUUUUAAUCAAACAUAAAUGAAUUUGUAGAAGAAGUCACUGACCAUGGGAAUGUUGUUCUUGCUGCUGUGUAUUCAUAGGAGCUUAGUGAAGGCAAACUUACCAACACAAAUAAGCAAAGUGGUUGCAAUAAAGACAGAUACGUCCCAGAGGAAGUGAUGGUUAAAAAAAAAAAACUUUACAUUAAAAGAUAUUUAAUGUGAAUAUAGAAAUAUUUCACAACAUUGAAAGCACAAGCAAUAAAAGGGUGGAAGCUGACCCAAACUUAGAAGGAGUAUGGCAGUUUGCCGUGAACAUAAAAGAUGCUUACUCAGUAUGGUAAGUUACUUGCCAGAAAAAAAGGCAAGCCCUAUUCAAACUACUUUGUUUUUACAAUGAAAUAAAACACUUUAAUUCUAUUUCUAAUGUUUUAAAUUACAGUGUACUAAAUAUUUUUAAACAUUUUUGCAUUUUUUUCUACAUUUAUAACUGGUCUUAAGAGUUUUUAAUAUUUGAGCAGAACCUUAAAGGUCAUGGAACAAUCAUCAUUUUCCCUAUUGAUUAUUAAGAUUGCAGGACCAUUUUUAUGGUCCCACAGUACCAUGUGAAAUGAGGAUCGCUUGUAGCUGGGAACAGUGCUUACUUCAGGGAAAACUGAUUUUGAUAGAACCGACUAGUUGAGUAUUAAACUGUUUUGGAAAUAAUUUAUAUAUCUAAGUGCUGAAAUAUAUUUCUCUUCUCCCCACUUAUUCAAAUAAAAAAGUUUUAAUACUA